AGCACAGAGUUGGGAGUGACUCCAGAGCCUCCAGCAAGAUGCUACUGAUUCUGCUGUCGGUGGCCCUGCUGGCCCUGAGCUCAGCUCAGAGCUUAAAUGAAGAUGUCAGCCAGGAAGAAUCUCCCUCCGUAAUAUCAGGAAAGCCAGAAGGACGACGCCCACAAGGAGGAAACCAGCCCCAACGUACCCCACCUCCUCCAGGAAAGCCAGAAGGACGACCCCCACAAGGAGGCAACCAGUCCCAAGGUCCCCCACCUCGUCCAGGAAAGCCAGAAGGACCACCCCCACAAGGAGGAAACCAGUCCCAAGGUCCCCCACCUCGUCCGGGAAAGCCAGAAGGACAACCCCCACAAGGAGGAAACCAGUCCCAAGGUCCCCCACCUCGUCCGGGAAAGCCAGAAGGACCACCCCCACAAGGAGGAAACCAGUCCCAAGGUCCCCCGCCUCGUCCGGGAAAGCCAGAAGGACCACCCCCACAAGGAGGAAACCAGUCCCAAGGUCCCCCGCCUCGUCCGGGAAAGCCAGAAGGACCACCCCCACAAGGAGGAAACCAGUCCCAAGGUCCCCCGCCUCAUCCGGGAAAGCCAGAAGGACCACCCCCACAAGGAGGAAACCAGUCCCAAGGUCCCCCACCUCGUCCGGGAAAGCCAGAAGGACCACCCCCACAAGGAGGAAACCAGUCCCAAGGUCCCCCACCUCGUCCGGGAAAGCCAGAAGGACCACCCCCACAAGGAGGCAACAAACCUCAAGGUCCCCCACCUCGUCCAGGAAAGCCAGAAGGACCACCCCCACAAGGAGGAAACCAGUCCCAAGGUCCCCCACCUCGUCCAGGAAAGCCAGAAGGACCACCUUCACAAGGAGGCAACAAACCUCAAGGUCCCCCACCUCAUCCAGGAAAGCCACAAGGACCACCCCCACAAGAAGGUAACAAACCUCAACGUCCCCCUCCUCCAGGAAGGCCACAAGGACCACCCCCACCAGGAGGCAAUCCCCAGCAGCCUCUGCCACCUCCCGCUGGAAAGCCCCAGGGACCACCUCCACCUCCUCAAGGGGGCAGACCACACAGACCUCCCCAGGGACAGCCUCCCCAGUAAUCAAGGUUCAAUGACAGGAAGUGAACAAGAAGAUGACAGUGAUUCAAAUGAUUCAAAUGCCAUGACAUUGGAAGAAGGUGGUCAUAGCUCUACCUUUAAUAUACCAAUAAAAUAAACAGCUUACAAUUUCUGA